AUAUCCGCCUGGGCGUCACGCUUCGUGGGGCGGGACGAGGAGAAGCCAAACGUAAAGACACCAGGAGUUUCUCGGGCCCAGCUGUGGCUGCUGCCGGGGAGCCCCAAGCCUUGGCGGGUCCUUGCGGCGAAUAGGAGUCUGGUCAGGCGUCAGGCUAGUCCGACGAAGAGUGGGUGUGAUCAGCACUGGAAAAGAUGCCUGCCCCUGCUGCCACAUAUGAAAGAGUAGUUUACAAAAACCCUUCCGAGUACCACUACAUGAAAGUCUGCCUAGAAUUUCAAGAUUGUGGAGUUGGACUGAAUGCUGCACAGUUCAAACAGCUGCUUAUUUCGGCUGUGAAGGACCUGUUUGGGGAGGUUGAUGCCGCCUUACCUUUGGACAUCCUAACCUAUGAAGAGAAGACCUUGUCAGCCAUCUUGAGAAUAUGUAGCAGUGGUCUUGUCAAAUUGUGGAGCUCUUUGACCCUGUUAGGAUCCUAUAAAGGCAAAAAAUGUGCUUUCCGGGUGAUUCAGGUUUCUCCAUUUCUUCUUGCAUUAUCUGGUAAUAGUAGGGAACUAGUAUUGGAUUGAAUGAAUAGUCUUCCAUUUUGGAAACGUUCAUCCACUCUCAUAUUUAUUUUUUGGUGCCUGCAUGUUUGAAGACUGAAGCAGGCUAAAAGCUCUUGAUGAAAUUUGAGGGUGCUGAAGAUGUUCCCACUAAUUUCCAGCCAUCACCUUUGGUGGGGUGGGCUUCGGAGGACAGUCUGUCUGAACCUGCCAGUGCUGACCCUGCAGCACUUUCAGCAUAUGCACAUCAAAGUUGGAGACCGCGCUGAACUUAGGAGGGCCUUCACACAGACUGAUGUGGCUACCUUCUCAGAAUUAACAGGGGAUGUCAAUCCUUUGCAUUUGAAUGAAGACUUUGCAAAACACACCAAGUUUGGAAAUACAAUUGUACAUGGAGUUUUGAUCAACGGACUUAUCUCAGCUCUCCUAGGAACUAAAAUGCCAGGGCCAGGCUGUGUAUUUCUUUCCCAGGAAAUUAGCUUUCCAGCCCCUUUAUAUAUUGGAGAAGUUGUUUUAGCUUCUGCAGAAGUGAAAAAGCUGAAGCGGUUCAUUGCUAUUAUUGCAGUGUCAUGUUCUGUAAUAGAAAGUAAAAAGACUGUUAUGGAAGGCUGGGUUAAAGUUAUGGUUCCAGAAGCUUCCAAAUCCUGAAAUAGAUGUUUUAAAGAUGCAACCUCAAACACCAAUGCUGUUGUUAAAGAGCCUAUGGGGAAUUGCUGCUCUUUACCAAAGAAUGGUUGAUAGGCCCAGAAGCCCAUCUUAGUUAGGGGAAGGGAGCAGGAAGAGGGUUGUUCAAAUGCCCACUUUCCAGUUUGGCCUUAUGCUUCAUGCAGACUUGAGUGUAUGCAGGAUUUCAUUAUCUGCCUGGGUUUUUUGUUUGUUUUUUGUUUUUUAAUUCAAGAAGUAGGCUGGGCCCGGUGGCUCAUGCCUGUAAUCCUGGCACUUUGGGAGGCUGCGGCAGGCGGAUCACUUGAGGUCAGGAGUCCAAGACCAGCCUGGCCAACAUGGUGAAACCCCAUCUCUACCAAAAAAAAAAAAAAAAAAAAAGUGCAACUAGCUGUGCUUGGUGACUUGGCCCUGUAGUCCCAGUUGCUUGGGAGGCUGAGGUGGGAGAAUUGCUUGGGCCUGAGAGCUGGAGGUUAUGGUGAGAAACUGAGAUUGCACCACUGCACUGUAGCCUGAGUGACAGAGCGAGACCCUGUCUCAAGAAAGAAGUAUUGGGAAGGUUAUUUAAAGACUCUACUUUUAAAUCAGGCGUGGCAGCUCACGCCUGUAAUCCCAGCAUUUUGGGAGGCUGAGGCAGGCGAAUCACUUGAGGUCAGGAGUUCAAGACCAGCCUGGCCAACAUGUGAAACCCCAUCUCUACUAAAAAUACAAAAACUAACCGGGCAUGGUGGCGGGCACCUGUAAUCCCAGCUACUUGGGAGGCUGAGGCAGGAGAAUCUCUUGAACCUGGGAGGUUGCAGUGAGCUGAAAUCACACCACUGCACUUCAGCCUGGGUGACAGAGCAAAACUCCACCUCAAAAAAAAAAAAAAGAUUCUACUUUUAGAAAUUCAGACCUAGAUAGAUUUGCAUUUGGAUAACAAAUCCCUACCUAUAGCCAUGUGGAAGCAGCUUGUCACUGUAUUUUAACUGUGUAACAAUUAUUGAAGGCGAAAAUAGAAGUUGGGUCAUCUUUGAACACCUACCUUUUAUCAAUGAAUAUUUUUAGACUGUUCUUCAGUAUCUGAGUCAGAGUUUAUUGUAAUUUGUUAUUUACACCAAGGUGGCAUCUUAGUCUACCUUCAGUGAGACUUGCGUUUCAGGGGAGGGGCGUAUGUGCAUCCUCGGUCUCAGUUAUGUAAACGGUCUGAUCUGUAAAAUAGUGGUAGCACAUGCCAUGUGGGAUAGUUGGUGGAGAUGAUAGAUGGAGUUAAGCACAGGGCCCAGCCUGUCAGCAGUAGCUACUAUUAUUGUUGCCCAUUUCCCCUGCAACUGAGGUGAGAGGUUUUCCUGAGUUUGAAGCUGACUGGCCCACAGUUAAACGUAACAGACCAGUUUUUCAGGGUGUCAGCCAACCUCUAUUAGUGUUCUUAAGUACAGUUUCUGUUAUAAAAGUUCAGAUUAUUCCUUGAAAAUUUGGAUCUACCUCCCAUUAUUAUGAGUAAUACAUGCUUAUAGUAAAAAAAAAAAAAUUGUAAGAAAUAAAUAUUAAGAAGAUUAUGGAGGCCAAAUUCUUAAGACUUUGGGGGCUGGGGUCAGGGAGGUUAUAUUGAAGGGGAGAUGUGCCUAACAUGUUACUACUAAAUGGCCAUCCCAACACAGCCAACACUUUUGUUUCCCAUUUUUUUUUGUUUCCCGUUUUUUAAUAAAAUUGAGAUAUAAUUCACAUACCAUAAAAUUCACCUUUUAAAAGUGUACAGUUUAGUGGUUUUCAGAAUAUCCACAAAGUUGUACAACCAUCACCAAAUCAAUUUUUUAUAGCAUUUUUCAUCACCCCCAAAAGAACCUCCCAUUAGCAGUCAAUCCAUUUCUCUCCUCCAGUCUUUGGGAAUCACCAGUCUACUUUCUGUCUCUAUGGGUUUCCCUGUUCUGGACAUUUCAUAAAAGUUCAUACAAUGUAUGAUCCUUUGGAACUGGCUUCUUUGAUAUAGCAUGUUUUCAGGGUUCAUCCAUGUUACAGCAUGUAUCAGUACAUCAUUUUAUUUUAUGGCUGAAUAAUAUUCCAUUGUAUUUACCCAUA